ACUUCCGGCCUGGGCGCCCGUCCCCCUGACCCCAGGGUCUGAGUCGCCGCUGCCGCCGCUGCCACCAUCCGCGAGGCAGGAGAGAGGAGGAGGAGUGCGGCGCGGCGGCCCCGGGACCAAGGAGGGACCCAGACAUGGAGCUGCGGGAAGAAGCCUGGUCUCCGGGGCCGCUGGAUUCUGAGGACCAGCAGAUGGCCAGUCACGAGAACCCAGUGGACAUCCUCAUCAUGGAUGAUGACGACGUCCCCAGCUGGCCUCCCACCAAGCUGUCCCCGCCCCAGUCUGCGCCCCCAGCCGGCCCGCCUCCCCGGCCGCGGCCGCCCGCCCCCUACAUCUGCAACGAGUGUGGCAAGAGCUUUAGCCACUGGUCCAAGCUGACGCGGCACCAGCGCACGCACACCGGCGAGCGGCCCAACGCCUGCGCCGACUGCGGCAAGACCUUCUCGCAGAGCUCGCACCUGGUGCAGCACCGGCGCAUCCACACGGGCGAGAAGCCCUACGCCUGCUUGGAGUGCGGCAAGCGCUUCAGCUGGAGCUCCAACCUCAUGCAGCACCAGCGCAUCCACACGGGCGAGAAGCCCUACACCUGCCCCGACUGCGGCCGCAGCUUCACUCAGAGCAAGAGCCUGGCCAAGCACCGGCGCUCGCACAGCGGCCUCAAGCCCUUCGUGUGCCCGCGCUGCGGCCGCGGCUUCAGCCAGCCCAAGAGCCUCGCGCGUCACCUGCGGCUGCACCCGGAGCUGUCGGGGCCUGGCGUGGCGGCCAAGGUGCUGGCGGCUAGCGUCCGGCGGGCCAAGGGGCCCGAAGAGGCGGUGGCGGCGGACGGCGAGAUCGCCAUCCCCGUGGGCGAUGGCGAGGGCAUCAUCGUGGUGGGCGCGCCGGGCGAGGGGGCCGCGGCCGCGGCAGCCAUGGCGGGCGCGGGGGCAAAGGCCGCGGGGCCCCGGUCGCGGCGCGCCCCGGCCCCCAAGCCGUACGUGUGUCUGGAGUGCGGGAAGGGCUUCGGGCACGGGGCCGGGCUCCUGGCGCACCAGCGGGCCCAGCACGGGGACGGGCUCGGGGCGGCGGGGGGCGAGGAGCCGGCCCACAUCUGCGUGGAGUGCGGGGAGGGCUUCGUGCAGGGCGCCGCGCUCCGGAGACACAAGAAGAUCCACGCGGUGGGCGCGCCCUCGGUCUGCAGCAGCUGCGGACAGAGCUACUACCGCGCGGGCGGGGAGGAGGAGGACGACGACGACGAGGCCGCGGGCGGGCGGUGCCCCGAGUGCCGCGGUGGGGAGGGCCGGUAGGGGAGGGGCCCGGGGGGGGGGGCGGGCAGGGCCCCUCGGGCUUGGCGGGAGCGACGACGUGCAAGACCAAGAGACCCAGGGAGAAGCGGACGGGGUGCGAUGGACCCCGCGGCAUCCCCGGCUCCCCGCCCUCCUCUGUCCCUGCGCCGUCCGUGGGGGGGCACUGGGGCGUAUUAGGGCCCGUUCACUUCUCCGCCUCGAGACUCUGCCCCCUCAGCCUGGCCCGCCCUUCCUAAGUUAUCGGCCUGCGAGCCGGAGAGACAAUGGAGAGAACUGCAGAGGCCGAGUGGCGACCAGGCCCCAAGCGGAAGGCCAUUUUCCCUGCUCUUCCUCAGUUGUCCGGGGCGGGGGUGGGGGGUGCUGCGAGGAAUGGAGAAACCAGGCCCUUUAGAGGAUCCCAGAGAGGGAAGAGAACCAGGGGCCCUUUUCUCUUUUAGAAUUUUCUUUUAAUCAGCCCACCUUUUGACUCCCCGCCCGCCCCAAUCCAUUAUUUUUUUCUGCCUUCCGGGUCCCAUCCUUAGAGCUCGAGUCGUUCCUUCCCCUCCUGGAUUCCGGGUAGCAGAGGCAGCGCCGCAGGAGGCGGGUGCCCGUUUGUCCCAGGCCUGGGCGUGGUGGAGGAAGGGGUGCUGGAACAAUAAACGGCACUAUCCAAAUGUC